CUUUUCUAGAGAUAUCCCUCCCUGAACUUGCUCACACAGGUCCCCUAAAUCCUCUAGAAUCCCUUGAAGAAGACCCUCACACACACCUAAUUUUCCCCCAAAAUAACCCGAGCUCUUGCUCUGAGAAAGUCCUAUAAUUCUUUCUGAAAAACCCUCUCCUCUGACACUCUCUCAGAAGACCCCGCCUUCCCCAUAUACUCUUUUGGAGACUUUACUCAGCUUUCUCCUCAACUGAGAUCUCUGAAGAGUUUUUCCUAAAAACAUCCCUCUGUCAUCCCACUCCAGGACCAGUCUCAGAAGACCACACCUUCCUCAGACACUUUUUAGAGAAUUUUCUCCCAAAUUGCCCUCCAUCAGCCACCCACUCCCAGCGCUUCCUGAGACUUCCUCAGAACUUUCCCUCAGAUUCCACUUCUGACAUCCCCAAGAAACAUUAUUUAGGACCCUAUCAGAUUUACCCACUAACUUUAGAAUUGCUAUUUACACCCUCUCAUUUCCCCAUUCUCUUUCCUCUGAAGUCAACUCAGAGACCUUUCUCAGGGGGCCCCCUUUUCCCAUUAUCCCUUCAGAGGUCCCCAACAUUCUCCAGACUCGUUGCCCAAGAGCCUCUAUGUUUCCUUGUAAAGAUUCUUGAGAGACACCUUUCCCCGCCCCCUUGAAAUCCCAGUGCUCCGAGAUCUUUCUUUCAGACCAUUUUUCUUAGGUGCCAUGCUCAUAGACCCCUCUUCCCUUCAGAGAUCAAGAGACCCUUAACACCCUCCUUAGAGACUUAGGAUUCUCCCCAUUUCCCUUUCAGAAGCCUUCUUCCUUCUCCCCUUUGAGGACCUCCUCACCAAAUAAUCCCUUCCCCUAUAGCAGUGGUUCUCAGUGUGGUUCCUGGCCCAGCAGCAGCCACAUUUGUUAGAAAUACACAUUCUUGAAUCCCACUCAGAUCUACUGAAACUGAAAACCUGGGAGCAGGGCCCAGCAAUCAAGAGUUUUUAACAAACCCUCCUGGUCAUUUUGAUGCACACGCAAGUUUGAGAACCUGUGCCCUUUAGGAGGAUUUCCUUUUCCUCACUAAAAGCCCCCUGAAAGAUGCCUCAGGGUAUGCCUCUGUGCCCUACUGCCCACUGCUGCUUUCCUGUUUCCUAGGAAUCCCCUUUAUGAAGUACCCAUCCUCCAGAAAGAUUUCUUACCUACCUUGAAAGGAUCUUGGCUUCUCCACAAGGUUACUCCAUCCUCUGAGCAGUUAUUUCCGAUUCUACUUUUGAAUGGUUUCUUUUCAGAUCUUCCUCAGUGCUUUCUCUUUCUGGCUACCCCUCCAGCCCACUACCAGCCUUUGGUGCUUCUUUAAAUUGCUGCUUCUUUGAACACACAUAUCCAUCUCUUCUUGUCCAUCUGUUUCUUCACAUAGGCACCCUCCCCUUGAGGCACCCUCAGGAGGUCUUUUCAUUCUGUGUCUUACUGCCAAGACCCCUCCACCUCCAUUGUACCUCUUAGAACACCACUCACCUUCAACCUUGUAGAUUUUAAUGUACUUGUCCACUCACCCUCACUGGACUAGGAACUCUGAAAGUACGGGAUGUGUCUUGUUCUUCUCUGAAUCCCACAAGGUGGGAUCUACUCUUUGUAAGUUAUUGGAAAUCACUGGAGAAUAAGCAGCUCUUCCUUCUGCAUUUGGCCAGAAAUCUCCAAGUUCCUCAGAUCUCACUCCUCAUUCAGGUUUAGUACACCUUCCCUGCCCCCUCCUCUCCUCUCACCUCCCUUUUUUUUCUCCACACAGCACCCUUUGCCUUUACUCCUGCCCUACUUGCUCCUGUCUUAGGGACUUUCUUUGUGCUGUUUCCUGAUUCUGAGCUACCCCAAGUCCUUUGCCUGGUGACCUGCCUCACCCGUCCUGGUUGGCUUCUCUUAGCAGCCCCUCUCAGCUGCUAAGUCUGGAGCCUCCACAGAGCUCUUGGCAUUUUUUCAAGGGAUUCUGUUUCUAGGGCCCAGAAGGGGAAACAGAGACCCCAGGGUAAAUAUUGGGGCCUGCCUUCAGGGAGCUCACAAUACCAGUAGGGGGCUUGGGCAUGUACAGAGCAGAAAAUGAGGUACAAAUUAUAUGCUGUAGAAAUUCAGCAGUGAGAGGGAGCCUUUUAUUUGGAAAGACUUCACAGAAAAGGUGGUAUUUGGGCUGGAUAGUGUUCCAUGGGAGUUGGGACAAUGAUGGUGCCCCCAGGCAGAGGAAACAGCUUAAGCAAUGGGUCAAAGACAAAGCCUCCUCAUCUCUCACCCAUGGUAUCUCUUCUCUUCACCCAAAAGAUAGAGAUGAAAGAAGACAGAUUUCCUCCAUUUGCAUUGUAUUUGCCAGCUGCACUUUAGUGACCUACAGAGUAAUAAUAAUAAUGACCACUGGUUUUUGAAUGCUUUCUAACUGCCAGGCACUGUUUAAGUGCUUUACAUGUAUUCAUAGGAGGUAGGAGUUUACCUACCCUAUGAGGUAAGUAAACUACCAUUAUCCUCAUUUUGCAUAUGAUGAGAUUAAGAACAGGUAGGACUAAUAGAGGGUCUGUGGGCACUGUCCAUUCCAAGAUGGUAGUGCCUUGGGUCAAAAAGUUUGAUUUUUAGUUAAGAUAGGUUUGGCUGCAAUGGGGCAGUAGUUGUUAGGUAUGCAGACCCUGGGUCUGGACAGGAUUUGUAUCCCACAUUACCACUCACCAGUUUUGUACCCUAGGACGAGUUACUUCCCUGGUCUUUUAGUUUCCACAGCUAAAAAUAUGAAGGAAAUAAUGAUACUUUACUUCAUAGAAUUGUUACGAGGAUUAAAUAAGUUAAUACAUGUAAAGUACUUAGAACAAUGUCUUGCCCAUAAUUGCAAUGUUAGAAAAACAAUAAAAUAAAAAAAAAGCUCAUAUCAGCCAGAACUCUAAAAACAUAAAGUGAUAGAACCUUAGCUCAAAGUGGUUUAAUGAAAAAAGUGGGGGAUUAAUUGGCUUUUGUUACUGGAAAGUCCAGAGCUAGGUUGGCUUCAGACCUAGCUGCAUCCAGGUGUUCAAAUAAUUUUCUCAGUCAUCUCCUCCCAUUUCUCCACUGAGUUAGCUUCAUCCUCAACAAGCUUCUGCUUUGGAUGACAAAUAUGGUCCUCAGCAGCCCCAGGUUUUAACCCUACCUCCUUGGAAAGCCUUAGUGGAAAGAGAACUCUUUCUUGAGAGUCCCAGUUUGAAAAUAGUUUCUUCCUUGAAUAGAUGUGAGAUUAUGCCAGAAGAUCCUUAGAAACAUAUUUUGGGUUCUGUACCCUGCAACUCAGUCUCUGGCUUGCUGAGCCAAAUAGGCCUGUGAUUCCAUCCGAUGAACUUUCUGAGCAGUGAUGGCAAUCUCCCUCCCCACUGUCCCCCAGCCGCAGUCAUUCUCUGCUCUGUGAUUGUUUGGGUCUAGAGAGAGCUUGUGGCUGGUCUGACUCAACCACACUUUGCUUUGGGAUAUCACGGGUGAUAUGAGGUGAUCAGCCUGGCUUGAUGGUGGCCUCAGGGGAGCAGAAUCCAGGAGUAAUGGCAAUACCCUCACCACAGUUUAAGGUUUCCAAGACACAGAACUUUGGAAGAGAGUUAAGUAGGAUUGCUGUGAGUGGAGUUUUGUUUUGUUUGUUUUAGUGUAAACUUGUUGAAUAGAAGCGGGUUCAGGGCAAGUUACAGAACAGCAGUGUAUGGAGUAUGCAAGUCUCAAAUAUCUCCAGCCUGCACUCAUUCAUUAAUGCAUGGAGGCACUAUUCUAGGUACUGGAGACAGAGCAGUGAAUAAAACAUUCAAGGUCCUGAAAUUCAUGGAAUUUAUAUUCUGAUGGGGGGAGGAAACAAAAAAAUCAGAGUGUGAUUCAUGCUGUGAAGGAAAUAAAACAGUGUGAAAGAGAGGGUGGGAGUGGCCACUGUAGUAGACAGGGGGAUCAGAAGAGGCCUCUUUUGGGAGGUGACAGUUGAGCCUGAUAACCAGAAAGAUGAGAAGGCACCAGUUGUGGGAAGAUCUGGGAGUGGAACAUUCUAAUCUAAGCAUUGUUACAUGCAGAAAAAGGACCUCUGCAAGGUGGGGAAAUUUAUCACAGAUAUUUAUUGAGGGCCUGCUAUGUACCAGGUGCUAUGCUAGGAAUUGGAGAUGUAGCAAUGAAUAAUAUAGCUACAGUCUUCCCUUCUCUCAUGGAUCUUACAGUCUAGGUGUUUUUGGAAGAGCUGCAGCCUUUGAAGAAACAUCUCUUGAUGAUGAUAUCAUAGACUCCUUCCUACUGGGCAGAUGAGGCAGAAUGGGGCACAGGUGAGCCCAGAUCUGAUUGAUGAGAAGGAACCAACCUUGUGACGGUCCGGGGAAGAGCAUUUCAGGCAGAGAGGUCAGCAGGUGCAAAAGCCCUGCCAUAUGUUCAGGGAAUCGCAAGGACCAGUGUGGCUAAAGCCUAAGUGAGGGAGAGGGGUGAGGGUUGGAAAGGCUGACAGAAGCCAGAUUACUUGCAGCCUAAGGGCCACAGUAAGGAGUUUCUAUUUUCAUUUAAGGGGAUUGGGAAACUAUUAGAAGGGAGUUUUUAAAAGCAAGACAGCGACAUGAUCUGAUUAAUUUUUUUAGAAAGCUCACUUUGGUUUCUGGGAGGAAAACAGAGGGUCAGGACAGAAUCAGGAAGGAAAGUUAGGAGACAAUCCAUUUGUCCAGAUGAGAAAUGGUGACAUGAAUGUGGUGGUGGUGGUGGUAGUGAAGAUGUAGAGAAGCAGAUAUAUUUUGGGUGUACAGAAAACAGGACUUGAUGAUGGGAUUAGAGAAAGAGAGGAAUCUAGAAUAAUGAUAAUAGCCAAGUCAUUUAUGCCUCACAACUCUAUGAGAGUAGGCACUAUUAUUAUUUUCUGUCUUCCUUCUCAGUAGGUACUAUUAUUACACCCACAUUACAGAUGACAAAACAGGCAUGGCAAGGUGAAAUCACUUGCCCAAAAUUACACAGGUAGUAAGUGGCAGGCUUAUAUUUCCAACCCGGCAGUCUGGUUCUAGAGCCACUUAGGUUUGGGGAAAGAUAAGCAAGGCAUGUGUAGCUGACAUUAAGAAAAAAGAAAUAUCAAGACCUAAUGACUGGGUCUUUGGGAAAUGGAAGAAGUCAAAGAUGACUCAAAAAAAUGUCUCAGUUGUCCACAGAGAGGUGAUGAUUGAAUCUACAGGAGUUAAUUACAUGCCUAAGUGAGAGAAAACAAGUGUAAAGAAGGGAAAGGAAGCAGAGAAUAAACUUUUCGGGGGGAAGGGGUGUCAAGACAUUUAGGAGUGGGAGGAAGAAUGCUAGCUUCCUCUCUAUUCCAGAGUUUACCGGAGCUCCCCAUACUGUACUUAUCUUCCAGGAGGCCCUGCCUGGCUUCUCCUCUCCUCUCCCUCCCUUCCCCAGCACCAUUCAUACAAAAAGCUCAUUCUUUGCUAAUGCAGUGGUGUACAUGUUUUGUGUACGUAUUUCAGGAGUUUCUGGAAAUAAUGGUUGAUUCUUAUAAGAGAAGUUGUGCUCCCUUGGCUUCUGACAGUCUCUUCUCAGGUUAUGAAAGUGAGUUAACCCUAGGUAACUAGCCUGUUACCUUGUUCAUGAAGUGUAAGUUCUCAAAGGCCUAGGUCGUGCUGUAAAAAGAACUAGGAAUGGGUAAGAAGGCAGAUAGGAUCCCCUUAUUCAUCCAGAGAUGUUGGUAUUAAAGGGCCCUUAGGCCCAACUUUCACCUUGUUGCCCAGGCUGGUCUCAAACUCCUGGGCUCAAGCGAUCUGCCCACCUCAGUCUCCCGAAGUGCUGGGAUUACAGAUGUGAGCCACCAUGCCCAGCUUUCUUGCAUUGUUAAGAGCAAGCAAGAGCUCUGAAGCCAGACUGCCUGGCCUUGAAAAUCUCAGCUUGGUGUACAGUCUUGGGCAAAGUGACUUAACUUCUCUGUGCCUCAGUUGCUCCAUCUGUAAAAUGAUAAUAUAUUCAUAUAUGUAUGUUAUAUAUUUUUGAAAUAGAGUUUUGGGGAUCAAAUGUGCUUAUCUGUGGAAAGCUGUUGGCAAAGGGCCUGACAAUGUAUGAUGUAUGAAGACAUGCUAAGCAUCAUGCUUGCUAUUGAAAUGAAGUAUAGAGGAGGAAAAAAGCAUCAUGCGCGGUAUUUUUAAAUACAUUGUUUCAUUUAAUUCUUCUAACAAGCUUCAUUGAGGAAGAAACAGAGUUACUUGUCAUAGUCAAUACAGCAAGUAAGUAUAACAGGAGAGCCAGGAUUUAAGCCAGGUCUGACUAACUCCACCAUCCUGCUUCUGAAUGAAGAGAGCUGGACUCCAGAGGCACUGUUUAUGGGCAUAUGGGCCUUUUCUCACUGUUUGGGGCCAGAGAAGAAGCCCAGAGGGCAGUUUGUCCUGGAACAUCUCAGCAUUUUUUUGUUUUUGUUUUUGUUUUUGUUUUGAGACAAAGUCUCCAGUCCCCCAGGCUGGAGUGCAGUGGCGCAAUCUCAGCUCACUGCAACCUCCACCUCCCAGGUUGAAGCGAUUCUGCUGCCUCAGCCUCCUGAGUAGCUGGGAUUACAGGCGCCUGCCACCACGCCCAGCUGAUUUUUUGUAUUUUUAGUAGAGACAGGGUUUCACCGUGUUGGCCAGGCUGGUCUCGAACUCCUGACCUCAGGUGAUCCGCCCGUCUCGGCCCCCCAAAGUGCUGGGAUUACAGGCGUGAGCCACCGUGCCCAGCCUUUCUCCAGGUGGGAGUGCAGUGGCAUGAUCUCAGCUCACUGAAGCCUCGACCUCCAGAACUCAAGUGAUCCUCCCAAAGUAGCUGGGACUGCAGGUGCACACCACCACGCCCAGCUAAUUUUUGGAUUUUUUGUAGAAACGGUUUUGCCAUGUUGCCCAGGCUGCUGAUCUGGAACCUUUGGCUUUUGUUUUGUUUUGUUUUUGUUUUUUGAGACAGGGUCUCACUCUGUUGCCCAGGCUGGAGUGCAGUGGCACGAUCUUGGCUCACUGCAACCUCUGCCUCCCGGGCUCAAGUGAUUCUCCCGCCUCAGUCUCCCAAGUAGCUGGGGUUACAGGUGCACGCCACCACGCCUGGCUAAUUUUUUUGUAAUUUUUGUAGAGACGGGGUUUCACUGUGUUGCCCAGGCUGGUCUCGAGCUCCUGAGCUCAAGCGAUCCACCCGCCCAUGCCUCCCAGAGUGCUGGGAUUACAGGCGUGAGCCACUGCACCCAGCCCUCUUAGCCAUUUUGUUAACCUCAUUUCCCACCUCUGGAGGUGGUAGGGGCUUCCCAAGAAGAUCACUUGGACCUCUUCAAGUAUGGUGGCAAUAUUGCUGGGCUGUUGGAGAGACUUCUGUUAUAGAGGCUCCCCUCUUGUGUUUUUCCUCAAAGGCAAGGAGUCAUUUUUGGUCACAUGAGGACAAAGAGACCAGACCAGUAGUGCAUUCUGUUUUGCAUGGGAAUUGUCAAGGCUCUUUCAGUUUUAACUGAAACCCAACUCAAACUGGCCUAAGUCAAAAACGAAUUUAUUCAUCUAUGUAACUGAAAAGAGUGGGCCACAAGGGGGAGGCUUCAGGCUAGCUGCAUCUAGGUUUUAAAUCAUGUGAACAGAUCUCCCUUUCCCCCUCCCCCAUCUCUUGACUUUGCUGUCAUCUGUUAGUUUCAUUCUGAAGCAGGCUUCCACCGUGAAAUAGAAGAGGUGGCAACUGGUGACAUCAUGAGACGAUGUGUAAUCUGAGCAACCCUAACCAAGAACUUAUUUUCCUUAGUAGUUCCAGCAAAAAUCCAGAGAGGACUAUCCUUGGCCAGGCUUUACCCCAUGUCCACUUCUGGAGCCAAGAAAGACAGUUCCUUCUCCAAGGGGAACCCAGGGUGUUGAUACUAGAAGAUGGAAAUGGAUACAGUAAGAUGCUGCCACAGUGAGAUGCCUCACCCAGGUCUCCCUCUGUCACUUCAGCCAAGCACAUGGGAUAGAAAGUAGCAGGCGGCCUCUGGCCCUUUAAUGGAAGAGGGCCAUCCAGUCCUCUCCAGUUAACAUCUAGACCGAACACAAAGCAUCCUUCUCUCAUCCAGAAGACAUAGGAACCCUACCUUCAGGGAUGAUUUUUUUUUAACAGUGAAAUCUUAAAAGUAACUGUUUCACUAAAGCCUCCAGUAUUUACUGAAGACUGUCAGAAUCAUCCUCCAUCACUAGAUCUUCUCCACCAGUCAUGUUCCCUGAGCAGUGGGGUGGCUUGAAGGUAUAAACCAGAGAGGCCCAAGGGAGGGAUAGUUAGCAGACUUCUGGUCUUUUUCUAGUUUGUGCUCUUCUGUUCCAAGGACCACAGGUAUGUCUUCUUCUGUGUAGUUGUUCACUAUUGUUUCAAUGUGAUUCGUUUCCCACAUUUGAAAAUAGGGGGGGAUUUUACUUUAAAAUUCAGAUAUCUGGCUCCUCUUUAGGGGAAAAAAAAAAAAAAAAAAACCUAAGACGUAACAAUACUGGACCCACAUUCCUUCAUGGUAGCAGUUGAUAAGAGGUGGAUAGUGACUUCUCCCUUUUGACCGGGUGUGGACUUUCCAACUCACCAUAGUCCCAGUUGGCCUGCUUUGUUCAAAGCCUGGCCUUGUAAGCAUCAUGUUUGAGACCCUAUUAUGUCCGAAAGCUUUGCUUCUAUCGUUUGGCCUGGGGGGAAAAGCUGGAUUAAUGUUUAGUCAGCAGCUUAUUGGGUGGGUGGAGGGGGGGAACAGUGCUGUUGCUUAGGAAAAGUAACAACCCAGUAAAAGAAUUUAUGGGAAAGAGUGUGCACAACUUUGGUCUGUUUGUGGAUUUGGUCGUUUUUUUGCUGUAAAUGCUGUUGGUAUAUCAAACCUCCUGUCACAAAUGUUCCCUCUGAAAUAGUAACAUGUCCUUCUAUCUUAUGAGUUGCCACCCAGUGAAGGAAUCCCUCCCACUCCCGAGGGAUGUUCAUCCAGCCUCCGCUUGACCACUUCCAGCAGCCAGGGAGCUUAUUACCUCCUCACAUGGCAGCCAGUUCCAUUCUUGGACAGAUGCGUUAUUUUAAAAUUCUUCCUUAUGUUGAAGCAGCUGCUGCCUCUUUGGGACUGAAAGCCACAAAAUGCUGGAGCUGGGAAGGAAAACCGAUUUUUUUAGGCGCGUGAGCUACCACUCAUCCACCCUGCAUCCAGGGCAAACAUUGAUAAUUAAUCACAGCACUCUUUCUCACUGAGUCAGGAAGUAUGCUGCCUUAAAAUUGUUUUUAAUUAAAUUCUUUUUUAAAAAUUACAAAAGUAAUAUGUAUUCACUUGCAACUAGUGAAGUAGUACAAAGUUAUAUAAAGAUAGUGUUAAUAAUCCCCCUGUUUCUCCAAGAUAGUGUUAGCAGCCGAGGGUGUAUUCUUCUAUACAUUUAUACACAUAUAGACAUAAAUAUUCAUAUAUAAGAUAUAUAAGGGGUUUUGUAUGUGGCUUUUUUUUAAUUUAAAAAAUGGCAUUAUAUUGUACAUAUUACUGUGUAGCUUAUGGACACCCCUCCAAGUAGUUACAGAUCAAACAUUGUAUAUAGCUUUGUUUUUUUGUUUUCUUGUUUUCUUUUUGAGAUGGAAUCCCGCUCUGUCACCCAGGCUGGAGUGCAGUGGCAUAAUCUCGGCUCACUGCAGCCUCCACCUCCCGGGUUCAAGCGUUUCUCCUGCCUCAGCUUCCCAAGUAGCUCGGACUACAGGCGCCCGCCACCACACCCGGCUAAUUUUUAUAUUUUUAGUAGAGAUGGAGUUUCGCCAUGUUGGCCAGGCUGGUCUCAAACUCCUGACCUCAAGUGAUCUGCCUGCCUCAGCCUCCCAAAGUGCUAGAAUUAUAGGAGUGAGCCACCACACCUGGCCAGAUUAGGCAUGUUUUUAAUAGAUACGUUAUAUCAUACAAUGUGGGAUCUGCCCCAGUUUAUUAAUCAUUCCCCAUUAAUGGAUAUUCCCAUUCAUUUCUUCAGGAUUCUUCUCAUCGCAGUGCUCCAGGCAGCCACUACCAAUCGAUUGGAGUUAGCCUGUGAGUAGAGACGGGAUUUCGCCACUUUGGCCAGUCUGAUCUUGAACUCCUGACCUCAAGUGAUCCACCUGCCUUAGCCUCCCAAAGUGCUGGGAUUACAGGAAACUGGAGAGGCGUGGCUGGACCAAGACCUCCCCCCAUGUGAGCAGGCUUCCUCCUCCCCCAACAACCGUUGCCACCACGCCCAGAAACGUCCUUAAGCCCUGGCCCUCAGGGGAAAGGUAACAGGAGGCCAGAGCCGGGACCAUGUGACGGCGCUGGCCCUCGCCACCGCCGUCCCCCGACCCUGGCCCCAGGCCCGGCACCAUGAUGUUCCGAGACCAGGUGGGCAUCCUCGCUGGCUGGUUCAAAGGCUGGAAUGAGUGUGAGCAGACAGUGGCCCUCCUGUCACUUCUGAAACGGGUCACCCGUACCCAGGCCCGCUUCCUGCAGCUCUGCCUGGAGCACUCACUGGCGGACUGCAAUGACAUCCACCUGCUGGAGUCGGAGGCCAACAGUGCUGCCAUCGUCAGCCAGUGGCAGCAGGAGUCCAAAGAGAAGGUGGUGUCCCUCCUGCUGUCCCACCUUCCCCUGCUUCAGCCAGGCAACACAGAGGCCAAGUCGGAGUACAUGAGGCUACUGCAGAAAGUGCUGGCCUACUCAAUCGAGAGCAAUGCUUUCAUCGAGGAGAGUCGCCAGCUGCUUUCCUAUGCCCUCAUCCACCCAGCCACCACACUGGAGGACCGCAACGCACUGGCCCUCUGGCUGAGCCACCUGGAAGAGCGGUUGGCUAGUGGCUUCCGCUCCCGGCCAGAGCCCUCCUACCAUUCACGUCAAGGCUCAGAUGAGUGGGGGGGCCCUGCAGAGCUAGGCCCUGGGGAGGCAGGGCCAGGCUGGCAGGACAAGCCACCCCGGGAAAAUGGACACGUGCCCUUCCACCCAUCCAGCUCAGUGCCGCCAGCCAUCAACAGUAUUGGGAGCAAUGCAAACACAGGUCUCCCCUGCCAAAUCCACCCUAGCCCACUGAAGCGCUCCAUGUCACUCAUCCCUACAAGCCCCCAGGUCCCUGGUGAGUGGCCGAGUCCAGAGGAGCUUGGGGCCCGGGCUGCUUUUACCACGCCCGAUCACGCACCUCUCUCGCCCCAGAGCAGCGUGGCCUCCUCUGGCAGUGAGCAGACAGAGGAGCAGGGCUCCAGCCGGAACACCUUCCAGGAGGAUGGCAGUGGCAUGAAAGAUGUGCCCUCAUGGCUCAAGAGCCUCCGUUUGCACAAGUAUGCAGCCCUCUUCUCACAGAUGAGCUACGAGGAGAUGAUGACACUGACUGAGCAGCACCUGGAGUCUCAGAACGUCACCAAAGGUGCCCGCCACAAGAUAGCCCUGAGCAUCCAGAAGCUGCGUGAGAGACAGAGCGUCCUCAAGUCCCUAGAGAAGGAUGUGCUGGAAGGCGGGAACCUACGAAACGCUCUGCAGGAGCUGCAGCAGAUCAUCAUCACUCCCAUCAAGGCCUACAGUGUCCUCCAGGCCACCGUGGCUGCCGCCACCACCACCCCUACUGCCAAGGAUGGGGCCCCGGGGGAACCACCGCUGCCAGGUGCUGAGCCUCCCCUAGCCCACCCCGGCACAGACAAAGGCACCGAGGCCAAGGACCCUCCAGCUGUGGAGAACUACCCACCUCCACCAGCUCCAGCUCCCACUGAUGGCAGUGAGCCUGCCCCGGCUCCCGUCGCCGACGGAGACAUCCCCAGCCAGUUUACACGGGUGAUGGGCAAAGUGUGCACCCAACUGCUGGUGUCCCGACCAGACGAGGAGAACAUCACCAGUUACCUCCAGCUCAUCGAAAAGUGCCUGACUCAUGAGGCUUUCACGGAGACGCAGAAGAAACGGCUGCUAUCCUGGAAACAGCAAGUGCUGAAGCUCCUCCGGACAUUCCCGCGCAAAGCCGCACUAGAGAUGCAGAACUACCGGCAGCAGAAAGGCUGGGCAUUCGGCUCCAACUCGCUCCCCAUAGCUGGCUCUGUGGGGAUGGGAGUGGCCCGGCGUACCCAGCGGCAGUUCCCAAUGCCUCCCCGGGCCCUCCCACCCGGCCGGAUGGGCCUCCUGAGCCCCUCGGGCAUUGGGGGUGUCUCCCCUCGACAUGCCCUCACCAGCCCCAGCCUUGGAGGCCAGGGCCGACAGAACCUGUGGUUUGCCAACCCUGGAGGCAGCAACAGCAUGCCCAGUCAGAGCCGCAGCUCUGUGCAGCGCACCCACUCGCUCCCGGUCCACUCGUCACCCCAGGCCAUUCUCAUGUUCCCUCCAGACUGCCCGGUUCCUGGGCCUGACCUGGAGAUCAAUCCCACUCUGGAGUCUCUGUGUCUGAGCAUGACAGAACACGCCUUGGGUGAUGGGACAGACAAAACCUCCACCAUCUGACGGGACCCACAGCCCAGCGCACCCAUAGGCUCCCUGGGCGGCGGGCGGGGGCCAACCCCCAACGGGCUUCUCCGCGACAGCGAGAGGGUGGGCUGGCUCAGCUAUAUAUUCUAAUAUUUUUCUACUCUCUUACCCUCUUAACUUUUGUUUAACAUUGGCACAUGCCUUGCUCACUCCCAGGCCCGUCGAGGGAUCUCUGCUGAGGCCCGGGGAGUUGGGGGCAGCCAGGAUAAAGGGGGCAGGGACUGGCCAGACUGCCUGCCUCUCUCCUUUCCUUCCUCAUCCCCACCUGGUCCCAUCCCACCCCUGCCUCCUCCAGACCGCUGACCACCUGCCUCUCCCCAAGGGAGCAGACUCCCCAGAGACAAACUGACCACUACCUUGUGGAGCCUGCUCAGAAACAUUUGACAUUUGGGGUGACGCGCAGGGCAGAGAACCUGCCCUCCAGAAUGUUAUUGAGAGGAGCUGGGGAGAAGGAAGGGGAGCAAGGAGAGGAAGCUCUCUCUCCUCUCCCUGCUUCCCCUUCACCAUUCCCCACAUUCUGCAAGGACAGGAGCCACCUUCCUCUCUCUCACCUCCCCUGGCCCUGUUCACCAGAGGUUCUCUAUGAUUAAUUUCUUAGGCCUAUUUAAGAUACAUAUUUAUAUAGUUCUUAACGGUUUUUCUCUGAUCAUUUCCUCUCAUUUUUAGAAUCCCCAGGUCUCUCUCAGCCAAGACAGUGGCAGGGAGAGCCUGAACUUUAUGAGGGGAGAGGGCAGAGCCCCCUCCUCCAGACCCUCAAGCUCUAACCCAUUUUCCUCCAGCCCUGGCUACCCGGAUGAAGAGGUUGGAGGUGGGCAGCCAGGGUAGCCAGUGAGGUCAGGAAGUCUGUUGCCUUAACGUCCCCUUCCCCACGAACACACACCCUUCUCCGCUCCCAGGUCUGGUUGGUGAGACUUGGGAGUCAGGAAUAAGGGAAAGGGGAUUGUUUGGUUUUUGGGUUUUUCCCUAAGCCCCUCCCUUUUCUUUCAGCCUUUUUCCUUCCCCCAUUAUGUCAUGACCUCACUUAAGUGGAACACUAUAUCAUAACCCAGAGAUUCGUCCCAGCCCCAGAGUCCGACAGACUGUCUGGUCCCUAUUCCUAAUGAGGGGUUGUGUUGGGGCCCAGGUGGAGGGAGGGGAUUUGGGGGUUCAGACUGCGGGGAAGCCAGGGUCUCCCUCUUCAACGCCCUCCUCCCCCUCAACCCACCUUCCCAACUGGGACAUUCUCAAGCUUUUCACACCGAAAAGGAAAAAAAAUGUUAUUUUUAGAUACAUUUUAUGAAUAACUUUUGUUAUGAAUAUGGCUGGUAACCAUUGUGUAUGUUAUUAAAGAUACAAAAUGUUGGGAAAAAAACAAAAAAAACAAAAAAAAAAAAAAUUUUAAAACCACCACCCUCCCUGCACUAUCACCCCAUUCCCCAGACCUUCUUGCCCCCGCCCUCCUGGUCUGUGGACUUCCCUCUGCUCUGAGCCCAGGGAGGGGGAAGAAGCCAGGGGGUAGGGUGGCCCUGGGAACCUGGCUCUGGGUCCCCACUUCCUCUCCCAGUGCCGGGCUGGGUGGGGUGUCAGGUUUAUUUAUGUACCUCUUGCACACUCAUCAACCUAUGCAAGUCCCCCACCCCGGCCCUCCAUGUUUCUGUGCCUUUGCUCAUCCCCUCAAUCUCCCAGGGCUUCUCCAGUCCCCCUCCCACUAGCUGCAGGAAGUGGGAUGGAUGGGCCACCUCGUUUGGAAUCAGCAGGGUGUCCCUCUCAUGGGACCCUCCCCUCUCCCCAGCCUGUCCUGUCUUGUUCACUCUCCAUCAGGGUGAGCUGACUGUGCCUGGCACUGGGAGGUGGUGAGGGACACCGUCUCACACACACAGGGAGGCAAGAGCUGCCCCCCACCCCACCUGACAGCAGAGUGUGCAGGACGCAGGCGGCCCCACUCUGAUGGGCAGGACCCUGACCCUCUCCCGCUCCAGCCCCCUCCCCAGGCCCUCCUCCAUGAUUUCACCCUCCCUACCCACUUCUGUCCCCGGCCCCACUGGCAGAAUCAGCUUUGAGUAACUGUACAGUUUUUCUCGCUGUUGGAGAAGACUUAUUUGUUGGAGUUUCACUUGUUUAAUGGUCUGGGCUUAUUUUGGAAAAAAAAAAAACAAACAAAAAAAACGAA